GUGCUCUUCCGUACUCGGAUCGCUUCUUAGGAGUAUCCUAACUGCCGGAUUGUCAGUGGCUUCGCCCCGAGGAGAGCUGACUGCCCUGGGCUGCUGCCUCCGGCAGAGCUGAGCCAAAAUGUCCCCGGAAUCUAAAAAGCUUUUCAACAUCAUUAUUUUAGGAGUUGCCUUUAUGUUUAUGUUCACUGCCUUUCAAACUUGUGGAAAUGUGGCGCAAACUGUCAUCAGGAGCUUAAAUAGGACAGAUUUUCACGGCAGUGGAUAUACCAGCAUGGCUAUUAUCUAUGGAGUGUUCUCUGCUUCAAAUUUGAUUACACCGUCAGUGGUUGCCAUUGUAGGACCUCAACUCUCUAUGUUUGCCAGUGGUUUAUUUUACAGCAUGUACAUUGCCGUUUUCAUCCAGCCUUUCCCGUGGUCCUUCUACACAGCCUCUGUUUUCAUUGGAAUUGCUGCUGCUGUGCUUUGGACAGCACAAGGAAACUGCCUGACAAUCAAUUCGGAUGAGCACAGCAUUGGGAGAAACAGUGGGAUUUUCUGGGCACUUCUGCAGUCUAGCUUGUUCUUUGGAAAUCUCUACAUAUAUUUUGCCUGGCAAGGGAAAACUCAGAUAUCAGAGAGUGACCGAAGAACAGUGUUUAUUGCCCUAACGGUGAUUAGCCUUGUGGGGACAGUUCUAUUCUUUCUCAUUCGGAAACCAGAUUCUGAAAAUGUCCUAGGAGAAGAUGAGUCUUCUGAUGACCAGGACAUGGAAGUCAACGAGUCUGCCCAGAACAAUCUGACAAAGGCAGUAGAUGCUUUUAAAAAGUCUUUUAAGUUAUGUGUCACCAAGGAGAUGCUCCUUCUUAGUAUUACAACUGCUUAUACAGGUCUGGAAUUAACUUUCUUCUCUGGUGUAUAUGGAACCUGUAUUGGUGCUACAAAUAAAUUUGGAGCAGAAGAGAAAAGCCUUAUUGGACUUUCUGGCAUUUUCAUCGGCAUUGGAGAAAUUUUAGGUGGAAGCCUCUUCGGCCUGCUGAGCAAGAACAAUCGUUUUGGUAGAAAUCCAGUUGUGCUGUUGGGCAUCCUGGUGCACUUCAUAGCUUUUUAUCUAAUAUUUCUCAACAUGCCUGGAGAUGCCCCGAUUGCUCCUGUUAAAGGAACUGACAGCAGUGCUUACAUCAAAUCCAGCAAAGAAGUUGCCAUUCUCUGCAGUUUUCUGUUGGGCCUUGGAGACAGCUGCUUUAAUACCCAGCUGCUUAGUAUCUUGGGCUUUCUGUAUUCUGAAGACAGCGCCCCAGCAUUUGCCAUCUUCAAGUUUGUUCAGUUUCUGUGGGUCGGGAAUCUGCGCAUGGCUGAGCUGAGUCCUGAGCGUCUCUCCAGGCUGCAGUCCAUGUCUCUGCAGGCUGCAGUGAAGGUGUGUUCCAGGCUUCACUGGGGGAGGGCCUGCUUCCCUGCUCACUCGUAUAGUUGUUGCAGGAGUCAGUUCCUCACAGACUGUCAGGCUAAGUAAGGAUCUUGGUUUCUUAUGGCUAUUGGCUAAAGAUCGCCCUCUGCCCUUCAUCAUGCUACGGAGUAGUCCUCAGGGCAGCCUACGACAUGGCAGCUGUCUCCAUCAAAGGUCACAAGCAAGGACAGCUGGAGAGAACGAGAGCAAGACAAAAGCCGCAGUCUCUCAUAACUUCAUCACUGUUGCACUCUGUCUGUUAGGUGCCAGUCACUAGUUCCAGCCUAUUCUCAGGGAGGGAAUUGGUGGGGAGCAUCUUACAAGGCUGCCCACCUUGUCACCUGUCACACUGAGACUUACAUGGAAGGUGACAACUGGGUCCUGUAUUCCCAAGCCUCGCAUUCUCCAGGCCCUUGCUCUGUUUGCUCAUAAUGGAUCUGUACAACCCUGCUGGCAGAAGGAGGUGAAGCCACCUCUGUUAAUGACACUGAGAAUUUUAAUCUGAGGAAGCCAUGGCAUCUUGUCACCCCUAGGAUUCCUGGUGAUUAUUGUCAAAAGGGAAAGGAAAUGAAGUGAAGUGCUGUGUGCAGUAUGGCAGGAACCCAGCUUUUCCUAGGCUGCCUCCUACUGGCUUUGUGCUAUGGUAUUCAUUUUCAGUUUCGUACUCACUUUUUUGUUAGAGACAGGGUCUUGCUUUGUUGCCCAGGCUGGAUCACAGUGGCACAGUCAUGGCUCACUGCAGCUUUGACGUCUUGGGCUCAAGCAAUAUUCCGGCCUCAGUCUCCCAAGUAGCUAGGACCACAGGCAUGUACCACCAUGCCUGGAUAAUUUUUUUUUUUUUUUUGUAAAGGCAGUGUCUUAUCUUGCCCAGGCUAGCCUUGAACUCCUGGACUCCAGUGAUCCUCCUGCCUCGGCCUUCCAAAAUGCUGGGAUUACAGGAAUGAGCUACUAUGCUUUUUUUUCUCCCCCGCCCCCGGCCCCUGUGGGGAGUUUGUUGCGCUUUUAUUCAGUUCUUUUUUAUUUUUAUUUUUUGAGAUGGAAUUUCACUCUUGUUGCCCAGGCUGGAGUGCAAUGGCGCGAUCUCGGCUCACUGCAACCUCUGCCUCCUGGGUUCAAGCGAUUCUCCUGCCUCAGCUUCCCAAGUAGCUGGGAUUACAGGCAUGUGCCACCAUGCCCAGCUAAUUUUGUAUUUAUAAUAGAGACAGGGUUUCCUCAUGUUGGUCAGGCUGGUCUUGAACUCCCAACCUCAAGUGAUCCACCCGUCUCAGCCUCCCAAAGUGCUGGGAUUACAGGCGUGAGCCACCGCGCCCAGGCUUUUUUUUUUUUUUUUUUUUUUGAGACAGAGUCUUGCUCUGUCACCCAGGCUAUAAUGCAGUGGCGCAAUCUCGGCUCACUGCAACCUCCACAUCCCGGGUUCAAGCAGUUCUCCUGCCUCAGCCUCCCGAGUAGCUGGGACUACAGGUGCACACCACCAUGCCCGGCUAAUUUUUGUAUUUUUUAGUAGAGAUGGGGCUUCACCAUGUUGGCCAGGCUGGUCUCGAACUCUUGACCUCAUGAUCCACCCACCUCAGCUUCCCAAAGUGCCGGGAUUACAGGCUUGAGCCCACCACGCGGGGCUGCUUUUAUUCAGUUCUUGUGUCUAUAGUUUUGAUCUUGGUUGACUCUUUAGAUGACUGGAUAACAUUAAGGUCAUCUUUUAAAUUCUUUGCAUUACUUGAGUUAAAGAUGAAAUGUGGGGCCAGGCACGGUGGCUCACGCCUAUAAUCAUAGCACUUUGGGAGGCCAAGGCAGGCAGAUCACAAGGUCAAGAGUUCGAGACCAGCCUGGCCAAUAUGGUGAAACCCCAUCUCUACUAAGAAUACAAAAAUUAGCCAAGUGUGGUGGCAGGAGCCUGUAAUCCCAGCUACUCAGGAAGUUGAGGCAGGAGAAUUGCUUGAACCCGGGAGGCAGAGGUUGCAGUGAGCCAAGAUCACGCCACUGCACUCCAGCUCCAAAAAAAAAAAAAAAGAAAUGUGACAAUGAAAUAAAUAGUUUAAUUUUUAUGCUUGUCUUAUAUAUGCUGUUCAAAACUUUUGUCUUCAUACUUGUAGCUAAGUAAAUGCUGUAGCUGGGUCUCCCA